CUCCCAAACUGGCGCGCCCAAGCCUCCCGCUCCACCGUCUGCAUCCCGCCCACCUCCUCAUUUGACGGAGAUGGCUGAAGACUUGGCCAAGGCCACCUCGGGAAGAGGGGAGUCGCUUCGGGACUGGGGCUGGAGCUGGAGCGCCAGCCUCUCCUCCGGUUGUAGCCUCCUAGCGCUCCUGGCUGCGUCGCUGAGGGACCCUCCACCGGGAGAGCGCCUCCUGUCUUCCUCCCGCUCUCCAGAGGAGCCUGCUGGGGGAAGCCGGCCCUGGCCCGCCGCUGGGAGGCUCUUGGGUGCCUGGGAGGGCUGGUGGGUAGCGAGAGUCGGGGACCGGGCAAGGCUGCAGGGAAUUCCUGGAGGGCCCAGGCCGGCGGUCUGUCGUGCGGCUGUGAGCUCAGAGCGCUUUCCGCCCUCGGUGCCGAGGCCUGCACUACUCAGAACGCCAUACGCUCUCAACCGACCUCCUGCCUGGGACCCUUCUUUCAUCCUGGGGAAGGAGAGUGGGGAGCAGGAAAAAUCCUAUUUCAAGACCUGAGGAAGUUGGAUUCAACUUCCUAGAGGAUUCUCCUCCCGCUUCCCCAAGCUGCCCCCAGAUCUGUACGUGGGAAUCAGAAGACAGCUGACCCGUGGCCAGGGCCUCAGAGGCUGAGCACCGUCUAUUUGAGCGGCUGUUUGAAGAUUACAAUGAGAUCAUCCGGCCUGUAGCCAACGUGUCUGACCCAGUCAUCAUCCAUUUCGAGGUGUCCAUGUCUCAGCUGGUGAAGGUGGAUGAAGUAAACCAGAUCAUGGAGACCAACCUGUGGCUCAAGCAAAUCUGGAAUGACUACAAGCUGAAAUGGAACCCCUCUGACUAUGGUGGGGCAGAGUUCAUGCGUGUCCCUGCACAGAAGAUCUGGAAGCCAGACAUUGUGCUGUAUAACAAUGCUGUUGGGGAUUUCCAGGUGGACGACAAGACCAAAGCCUUACUCAAGUACACUGGGGAGGUGACUUGGAUACCUCCGGCCAUCUUUAAGAGCUCCUGUAAAAUCGACGUGACCUACUUCCCGUUUGAUUACCAAAACUGUACCAUGAAGUUCGGUUCCUGGUCCUACGAUAAGGCGAAAAUCGAUCUGGUCCUGAUCGGCUCUUCCAUGAACCUCAAGGACUAUUGGGAGAGCGGCGAGUGGGCCAUCAUCAAAGCCCCAGGCUACAAACACGACAUCAAGUACAACUGCUGCGAGGAGAUCUACCCCGACAUCACAUACUCGCUGUACAUCCGGCGCCUGCCCUUGUUCUACACCAUCAACCUCAUCAUCCCCUGCCUGCUCAUCUCCUUCCUCACUGUGCUCGUCUUCUACCUGCCCUCCGACUGCGGUGAGAAGGUGACCCUGUGCAUUUCUGUCCUCCUCUCCCUGACGGUGUUUCUCCUGGUGAUCACUGAGACCAUCCCUUCCACCUCGCUGGUCAUCCCCCUGAUUGGAGAGUACCUCCUGUUCACCAUGAUUUUUGUAACCUUGUCCAUCGUCAUCACCGUCUUCGUGCUCAACGUGCACUACAGAACCCCGACGACACACACAAUGCCCUCAUGGGUGAAGACUGUAUUCUUGAACCUGCUCCCCAGGGUCAUGUUCAUGACCAGGCCAACAAGCAACGAGGGCAACGCUCAGAAGCCGAGGCCCCUCUACGGUGCCGAGCUCUCAAAUCUGAAUUGCUUCAGCCGCGCAGAGUCCAAAGGCUGCAAGGAGGGCUACCCCUGCCAGGACGGGAUGUGUGGUUACUGCCACCACCGCAGGAUAAAAAUCUCCAAUUUCAGUGCUAACCUCACGAGAAGCUCUAGUUCUGAAUCUGUUGAUGCUGUGCUGUCCCUCUCUGCUUUGUCACCAGAAAUCAAAGAAGCCAUCCAAAGUGUCAAGUAUAUUGCUGAAAAUAUGAAAGCACAAAAUGAAGCCAAAGAGAUUCAAGAUGAUUGGAAGUAUGUUGCCAUGGUGAUUGAUCGUAUUUUUCUGUGGGUUUUCACCCUGGUGUGCAUUCUAGGGACAGCAGGAUUGUUUCUGCAACCCCUGAUGGCCAGGGAAGAUGCAUAAGCACUAAGCUGUGUGCCUGCCUGGGAGACUUCCUUGUGUCAGGGCAGGAGGAGGCUGCUUCCUAGUAAGAACGUACUUUCUGUUAUCAAGCUACCAGCUUUGUUUUUGGCAUUUCGAGGUUUACUUAUUUUCCACUUAUCUUGGAAUCAUGCAAAAAAAAAAAUGUCAAGAGUAUUUAUUACCGAUAAAUGAACAUUUAACUAGCCUUUUUGGUAUGGUAAAGAGAUGUCAAAAUGUGAUUCUAUGUGAUUAGUAUGCUAUGCUAUGGAAUAUACAUGUAAAAAUGUUUCCUUUUAGUUGUUGAAACAAAACUGGAUAGAAAAAUGCUGUUCAGAAAUAUGAAAAGUCAUUCAGUUAUCACUACAGAUCUCCCAGUAAUUUUUCUUAUUUAGCCCAUAAUCUCUUUGAAGGUUUAUACUAAUUCAGCAAUCCCCCAUCGUUACCCAUUUCUUACCAUGCAUUUCUCGUUCUUUACUGGGUCUAAAGGGCUAUGCCUCCAUUUCAGAGAGCUUCAACUACUUCUCUUGCAUACUUCUAAAUUAUACCAUGAGAAAUCAUGCCUAGUUAUUCAUUGUUAAUAUAACUGUCUUAGUACACCAUAAACUGGGUGGAUUAUAAACAACAGAAACUUCUCAGUUUUGGAGGUUGGGAGGUCCAAGGUCAAGGCACCAGCAAAUUUGGUGUCUGGUGAGGGUCCUCUUCCUCAAAGGGUGCCUUCUAGCUGUGUCCUCACAUGACUGAAGGGACUAGCUAUCUCUGUGGGGUCUAUUUUAUAAGGGCACUAACCCCAUUCAUGAGAGCAGAGCCCCCAUGGCCUAAUCACCUUUCCAAGGCCCCACCUUCUAUCUAAGACAAUCACGCUGGGAAUAGGUUUCAACAUAUGAAUUGGGGGAGGACACAUUUGGACCACAGCAUGAACCUUUAGAACAGGGUUUCUCAGCCUUAGCACUAUGGACAUUUUGGGCUGGAUAAAUAUGUGUUGGUACAGAAUGGGGGUAUCCUGUGCAUUGUAGGAUCUUUAGCAGUACCCUAGCCUCAACUCACUAGAUGCCAAUGACAUACCUUGCUUCUUCACCAGUUAUGAUAACCAAGAAUGUCUCCAUUGUUAAAUGUUCCCUUAGGAGCAAAAUUGCCCCUGGUUGAGAAACAUUGCUUUAGACAAAUUGUUAAGAGUAUCAUGUACUACACUUCUGAAACUUAACGUGAUCAUCACCACUGACAGAUGAUUCACAGAGACUGUUUGAAUCUUGUCUCACUAGUUUUUCCUGUGCAAAAAUAAAAUGGACAGAAUUGCA